UCACCAUUGCGCUCCAGCGUGGGCAACAAGAGUAAAACUCCACCUCAAAAAAAAGAAAGAAAGAAACAAUCUCUAUCUUUUGUGCUCAUUGCUGAUCAAAUCCAUGUAAAUAUGGCAAACCAGCCUAGCAUCUGUGGCAGUUGACGCCGGUAACCCUGUCAGCUGCUGGAUUGCUGCCUAGGGACUGCUUGGAUGCUUGGCAGUUGGUAGCCCUGUAAAUAGGAAAUAUCCAUUAGGAGAGCCUGCAGCCACCAGUCACAGAGUGAUUACACGCCCCCUGUAGGAGAUGUGAAAAAGAAAAAGAGGAAAUCAAAUAUUCUGCAAUCUUACAACUAGUAAUGAUGUAUUUAUUUUCAGCUUUUUAUAUACGUUUUUCAAGCACUUCCCAAGUAUUUAUAGAGUACUUACUAUGUUCCAGGCUGGUGGCUGAGCAGUGAACAAACCAACCUAGGUCCUUAUAUCUGGAAACCUUAAGUUUGUGAACUUAAACACCCAUAUAUACAAUUGAGAUCAUAUCAUAAAUAUAAUUUUGUAUUCUAUUUUUCACAUUCUAUUUCAUAAGCAUUACCCUCUGCCAAUACUUUUUUUUCAAAUACCACACAUAAUGGCUGCAUAAUGUUCAACUGAGUGUACAGAAGACAAUAGAUUUAUCUAUUUCUGUGCUGCAAAAAGCAUAAUUAUCUUCCAUUUCCCCUUCUAUGAAUAACUAGCUAUUUUCCAAAUUCUCCCCAUUAUUUAAAAAAAACCACACACACAACAAACUCUGGAAUGGGCACCCUUCUCUUUGUCAUUUUUGUUAUUUCCAUAGGAUAGAUUCCUAGAUUAAUUGAAGUGUUUAAGGCUCUUUAUGUACAGCUUAAUUCAUUUUCAACAUUGUACUAAACACGCUUCCUCAAGCAUAGCAGUGCGUAAUUCUCCACAAUCUCCCCAGCACUGAUAUUAAUAAUGUAAGGCAUCUUCUUAAUCAUGUGUGACUUUGCAUGGUGCUUUAGACUUCUAGACAUUCUCCAUCCUCGUUGAUCGUCUCAAGUUCAGAUAUAAAAUUUCUGCCUUGAUUCUAACACAGUGUACAGGGCCUACACUAUAUUCUGGGUGACAAGAUGGCUUGGCUUUCCUUUCCUUCUCCCCCUGCUCCUAAGCUGGUCUCCUCACCUUUAUCAAGUGCUAUUUUUUCAACCAUGCUUUAUUGUGUAGGGGCCAAAGGGAAAGUUCCUCUUUGCCCUCUGAAGGUUCACUGAAAGCCAACUCAUAAAAGGCAGAUUUUUGGAGAAAAGGCAAAUAAAUGGAUUAUUUAUUUAUUUAUUAUUUAUUUUUGAGAUGGAGUCUCGCUCUGUCACCCAGGCUGGAGUGCAGUGGCGCGAUCUCGGCUCACUGCAACCUCCGCCUCCCGGGUUCAAGCGAUUCUCCCGCCUCAGCCUCCGGAGUAGCUGGGACUACAGACGCCCGCCACCACGCCCGGCCUUUACCGCCAGUUUUCACACAGAAAAGCGGGGGGAACAUCAGAGUCGUGUUUUUAGGUUUUGUGGCUGGCUUUGGGGGUCUGGCCUCUGGGACUCGCCUUGGGUAAAAGGGAUUCACUCUGUGAGGAGCCUCGCGGGAGAAAAGAACUGAGACUGGAGGCCUGGGAAGGUCAGAGGGAAACUGCCUCCCAGGCCUUCAUUUUGGGGCGUUGUGUUCUGAGCCCCGAUAAUUGUAACAUCUUCAUAAGCGACUUUCUGGUGGUUAUGGUGAAUCGGGACACACGAUGUAUGGUGACCGACGGGGGAGCCGGGAGCCCAGCGGGGUUAGGGUUCAGGUGAGGGUUUAGGGUCGGGGCGAGCGCGGCGCGGCCCGGAUGCGCAGCGUCACCGCGCCAGACCCUCCGCUCAGCUGCCGUGGGCUCUCCCCCUCCCCGACCAUAGACGGCGCAGGCCUCCAGUCAUCCCAGAGCGGCCCCGGAAGAAUCCGGGCGGAACCGCGGCUGGCUUCCGGUUCCCGGCGUUCUCGGAGGCGUACUGAGGCCCCGCAGGGGGCGGGGAAGCCUGCGUGUGCGCAGCUCGGCCCGGCCCGCCCUCUUCAUCCUAGCCCGCCCCCUCCCCGGCUCUGGACCCGGUUCUGUGGGAGGGUCCGUUCCGGGCUCGGUGCGACUGCGCAGCUCCUCGGCGCUUCCUCGGUGGCUUCCCCGGGUCGAGCAAACAGGUGGGGCAGUGUCGGACCAGGAAGGAGCGCCAAGCGGGCAGGCAGGCGGGGAGGGCGCGGGGAGGGCGCGGGGAGGCGGCGGCCAGUCCAGGAGGAGCCUGUUCUGGGUGCCGCGGGAGCCACCGACGGGCUGCAGAGGCCGGGAGGAGGCGACCGCGGCGCGGCCCUAGAAGGCUGGACUGAGGACCACAGCUGGCUUCCGGCCUCUCCCCGGAGCCUGGGGCCUUCGGCAGCAUCCCCGCGGCCUCCUUCUCACGUCCUCAGCCUUGGUAAGUUCGGGGAGACUUCAGGCCAGGGCAGUCUCCUGUCUUCUCUUGGAAACCACAGCAGCCCAUGCACACAGAAUGGCAGCCACAUUCCAGCUUCCAGGGCACCAGGAGAUGCCGCUGACCUUCCAGGAUGUGGCCGUGUACUUCUCUCAGGCGGAGGGGCGGCAGCUGGGCCCCCAGCAGCGGGCGCUCUACCGGGAUGUGAUGCUGGAGAACUAUGGGAACGUGGCCUCUCUGGGAUUCCCUGUCCCUAAGCCGGAGUUGAUCUCCCAGCUGGAGCAGGGGAAGGAACUUUGGGUCCUGAAUCUUCUGGGAGCUGAGGAACCAGAUAUCUUGAAAAGCUGCCAGAAAGAUUCUGAGGUUGGGACCAAGAAGGAACUAUCUAUUUUAAACCAAAAAUUUUCCGAAGAAGUAAAAACCCCAGAAUUUGUAUCAAGAAGACUCUUAAGGGAUAAUGCACAGGCCGCUGAGUUUCGGGAAGCAUGGGGCCGUGAGGGCAAACUCAAAGAGCGCGUGGGAAAUUCUGCCGGGCAGAGUUUGAACAAACCCAAUAUUCACAAGAGAGUUUUAACAGAAGCUACCGUGGGCAGGGAAAGAUCUUUGGGAGAAAGAACCCAAGAGUGUAGUGCAUUUGAUAGAAACUUGAAUCUGGACCAAAAUGUUGUUAGACUUCAAAGAAAUAAAACAGGAGAGAGGGUCUUUAAAUGUGAUAUAUGCAGCAAAACCUUCAAAUAUAAUUCAGACCUAAGUAGACACCAGAGAAGUCACACUGGGGAGAAGCCGUACGAAUGUGGCCGGUGUGGGCGAGCCUUUACUCACAGCUCAAAUCUUGUUCUGCACCAUCACAUUCACACUGGAAAUAAACCAUUUAAAUGUGAUGAAUGUGGGAAAACUUUUGGACUCAAUUCUCACCUCCGUCUUCAUCGGAGAAUUCACACUGGAGAAAAACCCUUUGGCUGUGGUGAGUGUGGGAAGGCUUUCAGUCGAAGCUCAACUCUUAUUCAACAUCGGAUCAUUCACACAGGAGAGAAACCCUACAAGUGUAAUGAAUGUGGAAGAGGCUUUAGCCAGAGCCCCCAGUUAACUCAGCAUCAGAGAAUUCACACUGGAGAGAAGCCGCAUGAAUGCAGUCACUGUGGGAAGGCCUUCAGUCGAAGCUCCAGCCUUAUUCAGCAUGAGAGAAUUCACACUGGAGAGAAGCCCCAUAAAUGCAAUCAGUGUGGGAAGGCCUUCAGUCAGAGCUCAAGCCUUUUCCUCCAUCAUCGGGUUCAUACUGGAGAGAAACCCUAUGUAUGUAAUGAAUGCGGCAGAGCCUUUGGUUUUAACUCUCAUCUUACUGAACACGUAAGGAUUCACACAGGAGAAAAACCCUAUGUUUGUAAUGAGUGCGGCAAAGCCUUUCGUCGGAGUUCCACUCUUGUUCAGCAUCGAAGAGUUCACACUGGGGAGAAGCCCUACCAGUGCGUUGAAUGUGGGAAAGCUUUCAGCCAGAGCUCCCAGCUCACCCUACAUCAGCGAGUUCACACUGGAGAGAAGCCCUAUGACUGUGGUGACUGUGGGAAGGCCUUCAGCCGGAGGUCAACCCUCAUUCAGCAUCAGAAAGUUCACAGCGGAGAGACUCGUAAGUGCAGAAAACAUGGUCCAGCCUUUGUUCAUGGCUCCAGCCUCACAGCAGAUGGACAGAUUCCCACUGGAGAGAAGCACGGCAGAGCCUUUAACCAUGGUGCAAAUCUCAUUCUGCGCUGGACAGUUCACACUGGUGAGAAAUCCUUUGGAUGUAAUGAAUAUGGAAAAGCUUUCAGUCCCACCUCACGACCCACUGAAGAUCAGAUAAUGCAUGCUGGGGAAAAGCCCUAUAAAUGUCAAGAAUGUGGAAACGCCUUCAGUGGAAAGUCAACCCUUAUUCAACAUCAGGUAACUCACACUGGUCAGAAACCAUGUCAUUGCAGUGUGUAUGGGAAAGCCUUCAGCCAGAGUUCACAGCUCACACCACCUCAGCAGACUCGUGUUGGAGAGAAACCUGCUUUAAAUGAUGGCUCUAAAAGAUACUUUAUUCAUAUCAAGAAGAUUUUCCAAGAAAGACAUUUUUAAUGUGAUAAAUGCAGAAGACAGUUUAGCAACUGUUCACUUGACAUUAGAAGAUAAGAUGGCAUAAUGAAAGAUAUAUAAGGUCUAAAUAUUACUGGCAAAGUAAAAUAAAUAGUUCAGAUGACUACUAAAGUCAAAGUCAUUAAAUCUGGAAGUAAACACGAGAAUUCAUUCUGGGAAAUCAGGCUGUCUGUGUAAAGGUUACUGCUGUGCUCAGGAGUUGAACCGUGUGGUGCUGUAUCCGGAUACUCAUGACGAAUGGAUGGAGGGCGUGAAAAGUGAGCCCAGCUGGUGCUCUGGGUCUACCCUACCUGACAUCCUUCCAGUCUUAUCCUUUGUUUCCUAUCCAGGCCCAGGCUUGUGGCUGAGAACAUCCACUUUCAGUCCCAUAUACCUGCCUCCAAGUGUGGUACAGAGAACUUGGGCCUGCUGGGGGCGCUUAGCCUUACUCUCUCCACCACCUCUCCCACCAACCCCCAGAUGAACUGCAGGUAGACGUUUCUUCCUUGCUUGGAGCCCCAGUUUUUGCAUUUCAUUUUCAUUAAAAUGAAAGGUGGUUUGGUUUUGGUUCUAAGGAGCUCUACAGUUUAACAGAGAGAGGGACCUUAGGGGCCAAGAAAGCAGGGGCCUACCAAGUAUCUCCACUUUUGAAAAUUGUAAUUACUGAUAAAAAAUUUUUUAAAGGCAGGUUUAUUGAAGCAUAAUUUAUAAACAAUAAAAUUUACUCUUUUUAGUGUA